AGACGCCCAGCUCGGCCGCCGGGACCCAGGUAGGACAUGGUCAGCUGCUGGCUCCUGACCCAAGGGGCCCCAAUGGUAACAACCCCCACAGAGGCUUCUCAAGAGACCAGAGAGGAGGGCGAAGGGCAUGGAUGGAGCCCCGAGGCGGUGGGAGCUCCCAGGUCUCGUGGGGCAGGGGCGGCAUGUGCAGGGUGGUGCCCGGGGCCUGAACCCAUGAAGACCCCACCGGACCCAUUCUGCUACCCUCCAGUGCCUCUGCUGACUCCACAUGGAAAAUUUCCAGUACAGCGUCCAGCUGAGUGACCAGGACUGGGCCGAGUUCUCAGCCACCGCCGAUGAGUGUGGCCUCCUGCAGGCCGGCCUGGCCUCUGGGGACGAGCUCUUGUCCAGUGACAUUGACCAAGGGGACAGCAGUGGCAGCAGUCCCCCCAGGGCCCCACCUCUCCCAACUGGGCAGCUAGCUGCAGGAGGGCGGAGCCGGCGGGGCUGCGAGGAGGAGGACGUGGCCACACAGCAGCCGGUCAGCAGGUCUCAGGGUGAGCCUGUCUUGGCCCUGGGGACCGGUCAGCAGACACCCAGCACGUCCGCACGGGCAGAAGCUCCACCGUCCCUCGGCCCCGGCGCCAGCCCUCCCAGCCAGUUCUCAUCCUGCCCUGGUCCGGCGUCUUCUGGAGACCAGAUGCAGAGGCUUCUGCAGGGCCCUGCCCCACGGCCCCCUGGUGAGCCCCCUGGGAGUCCCAAGUCCCCUGGCCACAGCACUGGCUCCCAGAGGCCCCCCGAUAGCCCUGGAGCCCCACCACGGAGCCCCAGCCGAAAGAAGAGGCGAGCUGUGGGUGCCAAGGGGGGUGGGCACACAGGAGCCUCUGCUUCUGCCCAGACGGGCUCCCCGCUGCUCCCUGCGGCCAGUCCUGAGACGGCAAAGCUGAUGGCCAAAGCCGGGCAGGAGGAGUUGGGGCCAGGUCCUGCAGGAGCUCCUGAGCCUGGCCCCAGGUCCCCUGUGCAGGAAGACAGACCAGGGCCAGGUUUGGGCCUGUCUACACCUGUCCCUGUGACAGAGCAAGGCACAGACCAAAUCAGAACCCCGCGCCGAGCCAAGCUGCACACAGUGUCCACGACUGUCUGGGAAGCCCUCCCAGAUGUCUCAAGGGCUAAGUCAGACAUGGCUGUGUCUACACCUGCCUCCGAGCCGCAACCUGACAGGGACAUGGCUGUGUCUACACCUGCCUCCGAGCCGCAAUCUGACAGGGACAUGGCUGUGUCUACACCUGCCUCUGAGCCGCAACCUGACACGGACAUGGCUGUGUCUACACCUGCCUCUGAGCCGCAACCUGACAGGGACAUGGCUGUGUCUAUACCUGCCUCCAAGCCGCAAUCUGACACGGCUGUGUCUACACCAGCUUCUGAGCCUCAGUCCAGUGUGGCUCUGUCUACACCCAUCUCCAAGCCACAAUUGGACACGGACGUGGCUGUGUCCACACCUGCCUCCAAACAUGGCCUGGAUGUGGCCUUGCCUACAGCAGGCCCAGUGGCUAAGCUAGAGGUGGCUUCAUCUCCACCUGUCUCGGAGGCUGUGCCGAGGAUGACCGAGUCCAGCGGGCUUGUGUCUACACCUGUUCCCAGAGCCGACGCCGCUGGCCUCGCCUGGCCUCCCACCCGCAGAGCUGGGCCUGAUGUGGUGGAGAUGGAGGCGGUUGUGUCUGAGCCCUCAGCAGGGGCCCCCGGAUGCUGCUCUGGGGCACCCGCACUGGGUCUCACCCAAGUCCCCAGGAAGAAGAAAGUGCGCUUCUCCGUGGCUGGGCCCAGCCCCAAUAAGCCAGGCUCAGGACAGGCCUCAGCCCGGCCCUCAGCCCCCCAGACAGCAACUGGGGCCCACGGGGGGCCCGGAGCCUGGGAGGCUGUGGCUGUCGGGCCCCGGCCCCACCAGCCUCGGAUCCUCAAGCACCUGCCUCGCCCCCCUCCCUCUGCCGUGACGAGGGUCGGGCCCGGGAGCAGCUUUGCCGUGACCCUCCCGGAGGCCUACGAGUUCUUCUUCUGUGACACCAUCGAGGAGAACGAAGAGGCUGAGGCGGCAGCGGCCGGUCAGGAUCCGGCAGGCGUCCAGUGGCCGGACAUGUGCGAGUUCUUCUUCCCAGACGUUGGAGCCCAGAGGUCGAGGCGGCGGGGGUCCCCGGAGCCGCUCCCGAGAGCUGAUCCUGUGCCGGCCCCCAUACCUGGAGACCCCGUGCCCAUCUCCAUCCCUGAGGUCUAUGAACACUUCUUCUUCGGGGAGGACAGGCUUGAGGGCGUGCUGGGGCCGGCUGUCCCGCUCCCACUGCAGGCCCUGGAGCCUCCCCGGUCGGCCUCCGAGGGGGCGGGGCCUGGGACCCCCCUCAAGCCAGCCGUGGUAGAGCGGCUCCACCUGGCUCUUAGACGGGCAGGGGAGCUCCGGGGGCCUGUCCCAUCAUUUGCCUUCAGCCAGAAUGACAUGUGCCUGGUGUUUGUAGCUUUUGCCACCUGGGCUGUGAGGACGUCAGAUCCGCAUACCCCAGACGCCUGGAAAACAGCCUUGCUGGCCAACGUCGGCACCAUCUCUGCCAUCCGCUACUUCCGCCGGCAGGUGGGGCAAGGGCGCCGCAGCCACAGCCCCAGCCCCAGCUCCUAGGAGCCAGGCCCGGGCCAGGGAGAUGCAGGAUGAGGAGACGACCACAGGCGCCCAGGGCAGGACGAGGUGCCGCCCUCGCCCGGGCCCUCUGACCCCUCUCUUCUACCGCGUCCAGGAGGGGGGCGUGUCCUGGUGCUGCUCCCUCCGACUCACCUGAGGAUCCAGCCAGUGACCACGGCCACUCCCCACGCCUGGGAGGGAGGUGCUAAAGUCUGGGUGGGUGGAGGGCAGGCAGGUGGCUGGGUAGGAGGGUGGCCAGAUUCACAGAUGAGAACACAGGGCAUUCGGUUAAUUUCAGACAGGCAAUAGUGGGGAGGUCAUUUUACUAAGAAGUUGUUGUUUAUCUGAAAUCAAAUGCAACCGCACCCUGCGUUUCUUCUGGGGUGCAGGGGGAGCUGAGUGGCAGGACAGGACUUGGACCUCGGAGGGGUCUGAGCAGCAAGACACUCCGGCUGGAGCUCUGGGCAGAGGCAGGGGAGAGGACACAGGGUGGCCUCAAAGAGGGGAUGGGCAGCCUCCUCACAGGUGGGCUGGGCUGGCAAGGGCUCCAAGGCCCAUCACUCUUGAUCCUCAAAGGACUGUGGCCAAGGCCUCUGCGGGCUCUGGCCUGAGACAGCGAAGGCUCUGCCUGCCCCUCCCCAGUGCAGCAGCCCCUGCAGGGUGGGGGUCUGUGGCAGAGCCGCGAGCCCCUCCCCGGGAGCCCUGGGUGCAGGUGCAGAGGGAGAAUUCGGUGGCCUCAGAUGGAGGGCUGGGCUCCUGGGGUUGUCCCGGGGGCUCCUGUGGGGCAGCUGGGGACCCACAGCCAAGAGGAGUCAGAGAUGAGGUGGGAAGGUCGGUGAGGGGCCCGAGGUGGCAGAGGAAGGGGGCUGCCUGGCUGGGUGCUGGGUGGGGGUCCUCAAGACUGUGGGAGACCCUGGCUGCUGAGCAGAGAACACAUGGAUGCAGCACCAAUAAAAUUCUAUCUUUUCUUUUUC